ACUAUGGAAACCCAGCUGCCAUCGCUAUGUCUCUGCAAAAGACCCCUCCGACCCGAGUGUUCGUGGAACUGGUUCCCUGGGCUGACCGGAGCCGGGAGAACAACCUGGCCUCAGGGAGAGAGACGCUACCGGGCUUACGCCACCCCCUCUCCUCAACACAAGCCCAAACUGCUACCCGCGAGGUGCAAGUAAGCGGCACCUCAGAAGUGUCUGCGGGCCCUGACCGGGCGCAGGUGGUGGUGCGAGUGAGCAGCACCAAGGAGGCGGCAGCCGAGGCCAAAAAGAGCGUUUGUCGCCGUCUAGAUUACAUCACGCAGAGCCUCCAGCAGCAGGGCGUGCAGGCAGAAAAUAUAACUGUGACAAAGGAUUUUAGGAGAGUGGAAAAUGCUUAUCACAUGGAAGCAGAGGUCUGCAUUACAUUUACUGAAUUUGGAAAAAUGCAAAAUAUUUGUAACUUUCUUGUUGAAAAGCUAGAUAGCUCUGUUGUCAUCAGCCCACCCCAGUUCUAUCAUACUCCAGGUUCUGUUGAGAAUCUUCGACGGCAAGCCUGUCUUGUUGCUGUUGAGAAUGCGUGGCGCAAAGCUCAAGAAGUCUGUAACCUUGUUGGCCAAACCUUAGGAAAACCUUUACUAAUCAAAGAAGAAGAAACAAAAGAAUGGGAAGGCCAAAUAGAUGAUCACCAGUCAUCCAGACUCUCAAGUUCAUUAACUGUACAACAAAAAAUCAAAAGUGCAACAAUACAUGCUGCUUCAAAAGUAUUUAUAACUUUUGAGGUAAAGGGAAAAGAGAAGAGAAAAAAGCACCUUUGAAAUUCCAAACAAAUUAUAUUGUACUUGUAUCUUUUUACCUAUUUUUAUACUUUUUAUAAUGUUUACGUUUGUCCUGAAUAUAUAUAUAUAUAUAUAUAUAUAUAUAUAUAUGGUAUAGGAGAUAAGCUAUUUCUUUCCAAAAUCUAUAAAUCUUUGAAUAUAGUCCCACAGAAUACUUAUGUUCACUUUCUAUUUUUAAAAGACUACUCUGAAAAACACUCUUGGAUAAUAAAUGUAUUAUGUGCAUACUUAUAUACUGACAGUUCAUACAAGCACAUGUGUAAUAUUUCUAUUAUAAGGACAGAUAUUGACCCUUGCAUUUCAUAAUUUUUAAAGAUAUUUAAGCUAAAAUUUUCUCAGCCACAUUUUUAUAUAAAACCAAAUUUUAUGUAAAAACUAGGCUUCAAUAAGUUAGCUAAAUUUUUUAAAUUGUAAGACAAAAUUUUUAUGGAAAAGAAUUCCUAUAUCCCAUCAAACCUAAUAAUUUUCCACAACUAAAAAUGAGUAUAAAUACAUAAUUUUAAGUGCAUCCUGUCAGGUCUGAUAUUUAAUUUUACUUUAGUUAGAAGCUAAGUAGUUACCCUGUUACUUCUUCAUGGAUGCUAACAGAAGACUUGAGAUUCCCAGACAGAAACAAAGGACUAUUACUCAUGGCACAACAAGGAGCAUGAGCAUCAGCACAUUCUCAUUGCUUCCCCUUGUCCCAGGUCCCAUGGGGGCAAAAUGAUAUGGCCAUAUGCAAUAUGGCUACAUAUACAGCAGGCUUUUGUUGUAGGUAAAGAAUACUGAGCUUGGAGGGUUCACUGCUUUUUAUCCAUGAACAGAAGCAAACCUGCUCUUUGCCUCAUCCCUUAUAGAUGCUCACUCAAAACUCAAUACUGAGAAAUGGCCCAGGUAAAGAACAGCCAAGGUCUUUCAUGCUUGCCACACCCAGCAAUAUGUUUAGGAAGGUGAAGUCUACUGAGGGCUAUCUCACAUCUAACAGUUUCUUUACUAGGACCAGAGACCAUUUUGGUAAGAUGCAGAUAACAACCCCAACCUUAACAACUUCACAACAUGAAUAGAAAUAGUGAUAAAUAAUUCAUAGCUUUUUACAAAAGAAUAAUGAGGUAUAAUAGGAAAAUGUUUUGAUGCCAAAAAUAAAAGAGUUAAUGUUUGGAUCGGACUCCAACAGGGCUCCUUAGAGUGAUACAAAUACAAAGCAAACGAUAUGUGUAAUUUAAAAUUUCCUAGUGCACAUGUUUUUUUAUUUUUCUUUUUCGAGAUGGAGUCUUUCUCUGUCGCCCAAGCUGGAGUGCAGUGGUACGAUCUCAGCUCACUGCAACCUCUGCCUCCUGAAUUUAAGCGAUUCUCCUGCCUCAGCCUCCCAAGUAGCUGGGAUUACAGGCGUGAGCCACUGCAUCUGGCCCUGUACGCACAUUUUUAAAAAUAAAACUUUAAAAAAGAAACAGUUGAAACUAAUUUUAAUAACAUUUUAUUUAACCAAAUAUAUCAAAAAUAUUAUUUCAGCAUGUAAUCAGUAUUUUUUAAAUUGAGAUAUUUGUUUUAUCUUCAAAAUUCAGUGUAUAUUUUUACAUAAUAGCACAUCUCAAUUCACAUGCUAAAUUUUCAUCAGAAAUAUUUUAUCUGUAUUUAAAUUUCCUAAAAUGUACAGUUGAAAAAAAGAGAUUCACAUACCCAGGUUGUUCUAGCAUGCCUAAAAAAUCUUGUAACUGGAUCAAGUAUCAGUUUUUAAAUUAGUUAAAAUUAAAUAAAAUUUAAAAUUUAGUUCCUCAGUCACACUAGCCAUAUUUCAAGUACUUGAAGGCCACAAAUGGCUUGAGACUACCUUGCUGAACAGACCAAGGUCAAACACUGAGAUAAUAAUGAUUCUUAAGGCCAUUUGAAAGUUAACAGCAAGUAUGUAUUACUGCUAUCUACAGUAAGAAUUACAUUUUAUCUACAGGCAAUCAUAAGCCAUGUCUGUUAUGCAGCAUAGGCUUUCCAUUCUCUAUACAUCUAGGUCAUAGAGUUUUUCCAUUGAUAAAUCUGGAUGUUUAUAUACCAACAGUACUUUCUUACAACAUAUUCCAGUAUAUAGUGUCCAGCUUCACCCACUUUUUAAAGUGGCCCUGAAACAAUUUUAUUCAUCUUAUUGGAGUGUUGCUGUAGGGGAAGAGUAGAAGCUAAGAAGAGUUUGAGUUCAACACCAUUAUAUCCAAAUCCUGACCUUACUACUGGAAUGUAAGCUCCUUGAAAGUGGAGAUCUUGUCUGUCUUGUUCACAGUUGUGUUCCCAGCCCCAGAGGUAGUCUCAGGGCCAAUAUCAAGUAUGCUCUCAAAUAUUUGCUGGGAAAAUUUACUAGCUGGAUAAAAGGCAAGUUACUUUAAUCUCUUUAAUCUUCCUUUGUCCUUACAAAUGAAAGAGACUAAUAGUACUUAACCUUGCAGUGUUAUUAUAAGGAUUAAAGUUGAUAAAUAUAUGAUCAUGAGAACAAUUGCUAGCACAUAACGGUCACUCUGAAAAUAGUAGCUGAUAUAUCAGCUGCAUUGUUUGAUUAUUGUUGGCUCAAUUAAAAGUUGGCUUUUCCAAAUCCUCCAUUAGGAAGAAUUUUUAAAUAGCCAUAUUGAAAAUAAAGUUGUCAGAAAACCAAUGUAACAUAUGUUGAAUUUUUAUUACCAAAAAGAAGUUACUAUCCAGUUGUACAGAAAAGUAGAAUGAGGUUGUGCAUCAAGAAAAAAAUUGUUCGUUCUCAACAAAAAUUUAAUCACAUGGGUAGUUUUUUUUUUUUUAGCUAUGGGUUCAUGCUGUAUUUGGUUGCAUCAUAUUUGAUAAAGAAGCUUCCAACUUAGCAUGAAAUACCUAAAGACAAUUUUUUUUUUAAGUUAGUAGGCACUUUUUAGAAUUUCCAGGAACUUUUAAAGAUGUUGUCUCCAAAAAAAACAAAAAAAUCCUGUAAAGUAUACAAUCCUACAUUUUUCUAUAGAAGAGCUUAGGGAAGAAAUCAUUCAAAGAUUGGAAAGACUUAUGUGUAGUAUUCUGUAUACUAAAGGGUAUCAAAUUUAGUUGUCAGUUGAUAGCAAUUUAAUUUCUUGAUACAUGGCAUACACUGGAAUCUUAUGAUGAAUUAUUUAGGGGACCUGUGCCACAAAGUCUACUAGAAUAAACCUAUCCUAAACUUAAUCCUGUUAGAAUUUCCUUCUUUUGAACUCUGUUUAAAAAAAAAAAAAUCUUUCCAGAAAGUAGGAAGUUAUAAUUUCUAUUUUCUGAAAGACAAACAAAAAUUCUAAAUAGGAUAUUUGAAACAGACCCACUGUAUCCUAAAUGGAAGUGCUAUUAAAAGGAAAUGCUAUUAAAAUAAGAUUUCAUAUAUUACUGAUAAUUCAUAAUGAAUUUUAGGAUUCCAUUCAAUUACAUACUAAAAAUUACAUUUUUUAUAGUGGCAAUGUACUUUUAUCAGUAUUCUUAUUUGACGGUCAAUUUGAGUUCAGUGUAAACAAAUAGGACUUAGAAAAAUAAUUUGUAACUCAAGAUGCUGUACCUCAUCCUAUAAUUGUUGUUUUGUAAUAUUCCUUCUCAGGAAUAUGGGCUAAGGAUAUCUCAACUCUGUCAGAUUUGUUGAUAAGAAUUUAAUAGUAAGGAGUUCUUAUAGCCUAUAAAAAGCAUGAAUUAUGAGAUCAAAUGUGGGAGUUACUAUAUGAUUAUCUGCAUUACAAAAUGAAAGCAAAUGCUUUAUUUAUUCCAACAAAAAAAGACCUAUAUAAAUUAGUUUAAGCUAACAUUUAGACAUUUACUAUUACAUAUAUGGUAUUUGCAACCAAAUCACUGAGUUUGUUGUUGUCGUUGUUUGAGGCUGUUGCUCUGUCACCCAGGAUGGAGUGCAAGUAGCUCAAUCAUAGCUUACUGCAGCCUAAAAACUCCUGGGCUGAAGAAAUCCUCUCACCUCAGCCUUUUAAGUAGCUGAAACAUUAGGUGCACACCACCAGGCCUGGCUAAUUUUUUAUUAGUGAUAAGGUCUUGCUAUGUUGCCCAGGCUGGUCUCAAACUCCUGGCUUCAAGCAGUCCUGCCUCAGCUUCCCAGAGUGCUGGACUACAGGCUUGAGCCACUGCACCCAGCCCCAAAUAGCUUCUACUCAUAACCUAGUGUGGCCUAAAUUUAUUUAAAAUGCCCGGGUAGGCCAGGCACGUUGGCUCACGCCUGUAAUCCCAGCACUUGGGAGGCCGAGGUAGGCAGAUCACUUGAGGUCAGGAGUUCGAGACCAACCUGGCCAAUAUAUUGAAACCCUGUCUCUUCUAAAAAUACAGAAGUUACUCAGGCGUGGUGGCGUGUGACUGUAAUCUCAGCUACCGGGGAGGCUGAAGCAGAAGAAACGCUCGAACCUGGGAGGCAGAGCUUACAGUGAGCCGAGAUCGCACCACUGCACUUCAGCCUGGGUGACAAAGUGAGACUCCAUCUACAUACAUACAUACAUACAUACAUACAUACAUACAUACAUACAUACAUACAUAAAAUGCCCAGUAUCUUACAAGACUGUAGUUCACAGUGGGUAAUUCAAAUCAGACACUGCUCUUCAAGAGAGGUAAUAUUAAUAGAAAUCUUUCAAGAAGGAUUGUUUUCUACUAUUAAAACAAUAAAACUCUUAUAAACCUGUUUAUCAGAAGGAUAUUUCUGUUUCAGCAACUCCUGGAAUCCUUCUUCAACAUCCCAACCAACAAUUACUCCCAGAUAGCCAUGUCACCUGUGAAUUAUCAUGAAUCCCACAUCAAAUGAACAAAUACUGCCUCUGGA